CAUCCCCAGCCAGACUCCUUUCAGCAUUCAGACGUUCCUUUUCUUCUUGCCUUCUCUACCACACUGUUCUGCCAUUUUUCUUCUCUUCUGUUCAUCUCCUCAUAGGUUCUGUAGCAUGGGGUCUGAAGUUUAUAUGGGCACAGGAUAGGGGAGCAUGGCGGGCCAAAAGGCAACUUUUGGGCAUGAAAAUAGGAAUGCCUGUUCCCACUUAGGGCCAUGGGUUUCCAGGCUUGCAGGUAGGGCCUCUGCCAGGGAACCACCCUCUUGUACUCAGUAUUUCCCUGUCUCCUGUCCAUAUCAUUAGUUUUCUGACACCUUGGGAACUGACAAAGCAAAUAAAGGCUUUGGGCCAAAGGGUGUAUAGAGUCAACCUUUCCAGCAUUGACAGGGCUCUGGGGCUACCCUCUCUGCCUCCAGCCUCUCCCUUAUCAGCACUGUCAUACAGCUUAAUAUGGUGAUCCUGACUCCUCUGCAGCCUUCUAGGAGAUGAAAUAUUGCCUUUAAACUUUUAUUUUACUAAUAGGUCAUUUUCACUUUACAAGUGUAUUCACCUAUGACUGCUGAGAUAUUAAAAAACAAAAAACUGGACUCUGAAAAAAGAGUCCUCACAUAUAAUUUGAGAAGCACUGCCUUAGAGGGCUUCUAGCUCUGUUCUUAUAUCCCGGUCAUGGAAAUGGAACAUUCACAGUUUUAUAUUAUUUCAGUAGAGCCUCAAGGCAGAGAGGAUACAGGACAUGUACCACACUUCCCAGGGAAGAGCUCGGGUAUAUUGUGAGCUUAUUUAGAGAUGGGCUUGAACACGCCCUUGAAGACCUAUGCACACCUUCACAUCCUUCAUAGUAACCACAAGCUCCAGAUGGGCUGUUUACCCCAACCCAUUCACCAGCCAGAUGAGAGCCAAGUUCAGAGCCGGAGCUGGCCACCAGAGGAAUCCAAGCAUUAGUGCAGACCACGGAGUGCAUGAGCUGGUUUACCAGACAUUUCCACUGGGCCUGGGAGAUGGGCAAUUCUAUUCAUGGACAGAUGGUUUGAGAAGAAAGGACUGGCAUGACUAUGAAAGCAUUCAGAAAGAGGCUAUGCGCUCAGGGAAAGGUGAACAUGGGAAACCUUACCCCCUUACUGAAGAGGACCAUGAUGACUCAGCUUACAGGGAAAAUGGUUUUAAUAUUUUCGUCAGCAACAAUAUUGCUCUAGAGAGGUCUCUGCCAGAUAUUCGUCAUGCUAACUGUAAGCAUAAGAUGUAUCUGGAAAGGCUGCCAAACACCAGCAUCAUUAUCCCAUUUCAUAAUGAAGGUUGGACUUCACUCCUGCGGACCAUACACAGUAUAAUUAACCGAACCCCAGGGAGUCUGAUAGCAGAAAUCAUUCUAGUAGAUGACUUCAGUGAGAGAGAACACCUGAAGGAUAAAUUGGAAGAAUACAUGGCCCGAUUUUCCAAAGUGAGGAUUGUUCGCACCAAGAAAAGAGAAGGACUCAUCCGGACCCGUCUCCUGGGGGCAUCUAUGGCCAGAGGAGAAGUCCUGACAUUCCUGGACUCCCACUGCGAGGUCAAUGUGAACUGGCUGCCCCCACUCCUCAACCAAAUUGCACUAAACCACAAAACCAUCGUGUGUCCCAUGAUCGAUGUCAUUGACCACAAUCACUUCGGGUAUGAGGCACAAGCUGGGGAUGCCAUGCGAGGAGCCUUCGACUGGGAAAUGUACUACAAAAGAAUCCCCAUCCCUCCAGAGCUCCAGAGGGCAGAUCCCAGCGACCCUUUUGAGUCUCCUGUUAUGGCUGGAGGUCUCUUUGCUGUGGAUCGGAAAUGGUUUUGGGAAUUGGGUGGCUAUGAUCCAGGUUUAGAAAUCUGGGGAGGAGAACAGUAUGAAAUCUCUUUUAAGGUUUGGAUGUGUGGAGGAGAAAUGUUUGAUGUUCCAUGUUCUAGAGUUGGUCAUAUCUACAGGAAGUACGUUCCAUACAAAGUUCCAUCUGGGACAAGCCUGGCAAGAAACCUGAAGCGGGUAGCUGAGACCUGGAUGGAUGAAUUUGCCGAGUACAUUUACCAGCGGCGGCCGGAGUACAGGCAUCUCUCCACGGGGGACAUCUCUGCCCAGAAGGAGCUGCGCAAGCAGCUCAAGUGCAAGGACUUCAAAUGGUUCAUGGCUGCUGUGGCCUGGGACGUGCCUAAAUACUACCCUCCAGUGGAGCCCCCGCCUGCUGCCUGGGGGGAGAUCCGAAAUGUGGCAGCAAAUCUCUGUGUGGACAGCAAGCAUGGAGCCACCGGAACAGAGCUGAGGCUGGACAUCUGUGUCAAGGAUGGUUCUGAAAGAACAUGGUCUCAUGAACAGCUUUUUACCUUUGGAUGGAGAGAAGAUAUUCGACCCGGUGAGCCACUGCAUACCCGGAAAUUCUGCUUUGAUGCGAUCUCACACAACAGCCCCGUUACACUCUAUGACUGUCAUGGCAUGAAGGGGAACCAGCUCUGGGGAUACCGGAAGGACAGAACAUUAUUCCAUCCUGUGAGCAACAGCUGCAUGGAUUGCAACCCCGCAGAGAAGAAGAUUUUCAUGGCCAGAUGUGACCCUCUCUCUGAGACUCAGCAGUGGAUUUUUGAACACAUUAAUAUGACUGUUUUAGAAAAAUUUAACCACCAUGCCAACUCCUAGAAAGAAGAAAGGAAGAAAGAGUGAUUACCUACAGGUUAUAAAUUAAAUUUUAGCCAGCAUCUGGGUCGAAGGAGUCAGGAAUAACAUUUCCUCGAUCCAGGAAGGCUGGUUUAAAAAUUUGCAAAUGCCAUGUCAAAGUAGGUUGUUUUGAAGAACUUCCUGCAUCUGAAGAACUUGGCUGAGAAUCUCACCAGCUGCUUCUGAGAACUCGAGACUAGCAGUUCCCUUGCUGGCCAAGGGCAAAGAUAAUUUAGGGACUUUUCAAAACAACUGCUGAGCUAAUAAAUCCUAGCAUUUCUCAGGUCAAAUCCUGCAGUAGUGAGUAGCUAUGAAUGGAUCCUAUUAACUGGGUGGGAGGGGGGUGAAAAUGGAGUGCAUGACUGCUCUGACAACCUGAGGAUAUCACAGGUUUAGAACUAGCCAAGCUUAAGGGGUGAGCUGUACUCUUUGGUGCCAUUCUCUGACUAAGAAUGGGUUCAGCAGGUUUAACCCUUAAAAGUGCUGCAGAUGAUUUCAGAGUGCUCACACUAUUCUGUUUUUUUUAUUUUUAUUUUUAAAUGAGGGUGCAAUAUCUAAUGUAAGACUUAAAUUACAUAAUGAAAUGGACAUCCAGUGUUCCCAUUCUUUCGUUUAUAUUUGCCAUUUUUUUUUCAGAGCAAAGUUUCUUUUUUAUGAAAGUUCAUGCUCCAUGAAUCCACUGAAUUUCUAAUUCAGUGCCCUUCUAUGAAUCCAGUUAAAAACAAAAGCAAAAGCAAAAAUCUAUGCUAUCAAGUUACUCCAAAGAAAGAUUUCACAGAAGCAGCAAAACCAUAUAAGAUUUAGGAGAGGGACUUCCCUGGGAAAUCUAUUUUUACUUUUCUAUUAUUUUUAAAAUCUUAAAAGUCUGAUAUUUGUCCAGUCAUAAUUUUUAUUAAGCAAGGAAAUGGAGUGAGUUUGAUGUAAUUUGUUUAGGAGAUUCUUAAACCCAAAUAAAUCUACACUCCAAGUGAUAUGUGAAAAUGGCUUAGUUCACUUCAAUUCUGUUUAGUCAGUGGUGGGAGCUUAGAAGUGGUUUUAUUUGUUCGUUUGUUUGGGUUUUGCUUUUGUUUUUUAUUUUUUUCUUGUUUUUUUUUUGUAGUGUUGAAUUAAUGAUGUUCUUUUAUUUGGAAGCUCAUAAAAGGAAUUACCAUUAAUAAAGUGUUUCUGACACCAUUUUCUGUUAAUGGGACAAUAUUUCGGGGAUGAAGAAAGGAAUGCUCCGAAAACUAAAUGGAACACUUAAUCCUUAAAGCAAUUUUUUACUGUUCAAUAAUAUCACAUUGGGGGAAGAAAACACAGGUAUCAAGGUGGUUCUUGGGAAAAAAGAAUCAUGUUUAUUAUAUAUCUCUCAAGUUUUUUUGGUAUAAAAAUGUUUUAACUUUGCUUUCUUUUUGGUUUUUGUUUGAAGUUGGUUUUCCUGUUAAUAAAAAUUUAUAUAACA